AUAGCUGCCAGGCACACACCUGGAGGGCAUCACAUGGCUGGUCUGGUGAGAGGCUUUCUGUCUUUGGAAAUGAGGGGGUGAAUUAAGGUCUUUACCUUCUCUAGCCUGUCUGAGCUCUGCUUUCCAGGGGAACCUAAAUGAGAGGUUUUCUAACCUUUUAAAGAAAAAAAAAAUGUGACUGUUUAUCCAAACAAUUACGAUGUGUAUUGUUACCAGUUUUCCAAGAUUUUUUAUAUUGUUAUUCAUCUGUGAUUCCUCAAAUCAAAGUUCCUUUCCACAUAACUCAGGGUAUCAUUCUUGUUUAUGUUUUCCUUUAUGUUAAUGUUUGUUUCCUGUUUAAGCUUCAGAGAAGAUGCAGCAGAAAGAAAUAAAUAUGUAGUAGAGAAAUUUGGAAGUGAUGAAGGAAUACAGGUGAAAGCCAUCGAGUUCAUGCAGCAGCUAGUAGUAACUUAGCUGACAACAGACCCUUUUGGCAGGAGCCCAUUGCUUUACUCCUUUUGCUAUAUAAUGAGUUCCUUGGUCCGAAGUUGGUUGUGAUACCAUGAUGGUGAAUAAGGAAUCCAGUCAAGUCCACAUUUGGUGAUGCUGGAGAAGUGUGGUGGGCAAAGAAGAUAAAUUUAAAUCCAGAGUGAGUUAUCUAUUACAAGGAGGACAAAUCUGUUGCCUGAAGCAUUUCAGGGUCUGCUUUUUCAUCAAGUUUCUGUAGGGGUUGUAUAAAACGAAAGUUACUUCACCUAUAUCCACCAACUGGUAGGGGAGAGGCAAAAUGCUAGUGGGACUCACAGCCUGGAUGUGCUGAUCUGACCCAUUCAGUCACCUGUGAUGUCGAAAGGCUACCAGCCAGGUCCGAGUGAGGCCAGGCUGUGGGGCCAGCAGCUGGGCUCCUGAGCUGUGCUGCUGCAGAUCCAGUGAUGUGCAGUGUGUUUUGUCAAGACAGAGUGCUUCCUCUCCAGUCUACUGUCUAGUAUCUUGUGCACUGAGUUUUUAGGUUUUAAUGACCGUAGUCCUGAUUUACAUACUUUGCAGUUGAUUUUUUUUUAGCCAUCUUUUAAUUCUGCCUUUUCAAUUUAUACUUUCUUAUUUUUUAAUUAGCUUUUUUAAAAAGCACCCUAAAUAUACUGAUUUUUGUUGGUUUUAAAAAUCACCUUAAAUAUAUUUUGUUGGGAUUAUUUUAGUGUCUUAAGUAUACUUUGUUAGGAUUUUUUAGCAUCUAAAUAUACCUAUUUGUUGGACUGAUUAACUUCAUCUGAAGUGAAUUUGUGAUCUAAUGUCUGAUAUUGUUAGUUGCAUUUAUUUCUUCAUGUACUUUAGAACUUUGGUUAAAUGACAUGUUUUGAAUGAGGUUUUAAAAACUUUUCACUCAUUCAGUCAUUUUUCGCCUCUUUCUCCCUCUCUGCACACUCUCCCCUGUGUAGCCUCAUUCUGCUUGUCUCUGUCUGGCUUCCAUGGAGCCUGGGUGCAGAACUAGCUUUCACAGUGGGGGCUUAGUUACCUGGGCAUUCAUGGCUGCUUCACGCAGUGCCUGGUCCUGCCUGACAGGUGUCCUCCAUCCUCCCUAGACCGCCACUCCAUAGGAGGCAAGGAUGCUGCGAGCCUUCCUUCAGGCAUGGAGGGGUAGGGCUCUAGUCAGCACCUUCCAUCCCACCUUCCAGCAAGGGUGCUAGUUUCUCACUCUGUCGUUUGUGCCUCUGUUUAGCCCCCAACCCUUCUAAGACCCAAACCUACAGUUUCAUUGCCUGUUUUUGGACCCUAGCAUAGGAGGGGCUGGCUGCUCAUGGUUUUGUCCUCGGGGUCUUGCCUCUUUGUGUUUCUGUCUCGUAUCGAUUUCAUAGAAAUGUUUAUUUUGUGUGUGUGCUUGCCUGUAUCCUUUUCCUUUUUUCUUUUUAUGUUUCCCCUCUCAUUGCUGUAUGUUUGGAGUAAAGAGAAUCCAUCCAAAAGUGAAUUUACCGUGCCAUCUUAACUGGAAGUCACAUGGGCAGAGAGUUUAAAGGAAAGAAAGAUACUUGGUUUUACAUAGUACUGAAAGCUAACCACAAGAACGCUUCCUAUGUGAGCUCAGUGACCCAUAGCAUAUAGUUACUUAAACUCCGUCUGAGGCUUGCAGGCCCCAAAAGAUGAGUGGGAUUAGGCAGGUGGGAUUUAUUAGGGUGCUAUGGUUCUCUACAAAGGUUUCACCUUCUAUUUUUCAUUUUGGUGGUAAUUUUUUAAAAAUUCAUAAUUCCACACACCUAAAUGCCUGCAAUUCUAACUAAGUAAUGUCUUAAAAUUUCAGUGCCUGGAGUUGUGUUUGUAUUGGUGCCAAGGAGCACUGCUUUAAAUAUAGGGAGAUAUUAUAAAAGAACAGAGGUGAAAAUGUAAAUAACGUGUUUGAGCUAAGAGAUUGCCGUUGCACAGUGGUUCUGAAGAGGAAAGUGAUGCGUGAAUUAAGCUGUCUCCCUGCAUGUGUUAGUAUUGGCCAGUCAACAGAACCUGCCUGUCGGUACCAAGCCCUACAUGGUUAGUCCAAAGUGAGUUUCAAUGACUGCAUCAUUGAUCACGCUGAAUUAAUUUUGUCAAUUUAAAUUUUACUCAUUUUGUAGAUUUGUUGGUAUUUAAUUUGUAUAUUUUUUAUAUUGUGGUUGUGUAAGAGUUACAAGCAUAAAGGUUUUACUGGUUUAUGUUUGUUAAUAUUUAACUAAUAAGAAGAAUGACUUUAGAUAAUACUGGGAGCUCUCAACAGUUUUUAAGUUUGAGAACCAUGGGUCAAAUGGUAAUUUAACUCUUGCUGUUGGUUGCAGCAAGCACCUUGCAUUUGAUUUUGAUGUCUUUAGCUCACUCCUGCUCAUGCUUCCUGACCUGCUUAGCUCAGGAUCGUUUCUCUCUGGGGACUCUGACACCUCCAUGCCGGGCUGGUGCCCCUUCCUCAUGCUGCCUGCAGCCCCCUGUGUUUCCUUCUCUCCCAGCCCUUCCCACAGUGUAAUCUGUGUAUGGGUCCCAAUUUCCUCAUUAGCCAUAAGUUGCUUGAGAGUGGGGAACACUGUCAUCUUUUUAUUUGCAGUGAUUUUCAGAGCUCUUGUCAUAAAAUAGGCUCCUAAUAAAUGUAUGGGUUUCCUUGUUUUUGUUUAGGUAGUAAUAAAUUACCUGUAGAAUCAAGGAGAGAAAGAGGCAGAAAUAACUUGGAGCCAAGUCACAAGGCAAGAAGAAGCUUCCUAAUAUUUUAAUAACUAAUGUGUUCCUCAGCUCACUUUCUAACUGGUCUAACCAAAACCCAAGUCUUACUGUCAGAUUUAAUGUGUGCCGACCAUUUCCUUCAGUGCUGGACAGGCUGCUGUGAAGGGACAUCACCUUUUCGCUUUUUCCAAGAUGGCUCAAGAUUCAGUAGAUCUUUCUUGUGAUUAUCAGUUUUGGAUGCAGAAGCUUUCUGUAUGGGAUCAGGCUUCCACUUUGGAAACCCAGCAAGACACCUGUCUUCACGUGGCUCAGUUCCAGGAGUUCCUAAGGAAGAUGUAUGAAGCCUUGAAAGAGAUGGAUUCUAAUACAGUCAUUGAAAGAUUCCCCACAAUUGGUCAACUGUUGGCAAAAGCUUGUUGGAAUCCUUUUAUUUUAGCAUAUGAUGAAAGCCAAAAAAUUCUAAUAUGGUGCUUAUGUUGUCUAAUUAACAAAGAACCACAGAAUUCUGGACAAUCAAAACUUAACUCCUGGAUACAGGGUGUAUUAUCUCAUAUACUUUCAGCACUCAGAUUUGAUAAAGAAGUUGCUCUUUUCACUCAAGGUCUUGGGUAUGCACCUAUAGAUUACUAUCCUGGUUUGCUUAAAAAUAUGGUUUUAUCAUUAGCGUCUGAACUCAGAGAGAAUCAUCUUAAUGGAUUUAACACUCAAAGGCGAAUGGCUCCCGAGCGAGUGGCGUCCCUGUCACGAGUUUGUGUCCCACUUAUUACCCUGACAGAUGUUGACCCCCUGGUGGAGGCUCUCCUCAUCUGUCAUGGACGUGAACCUCAGGAAAUCCUCCAGCCAGAGUUCUUUGAGGCUGUAAACGAGGCCAUUUUGCUGAAGAAGAUUUCUCUCCCCAUGUCAGCUGUAGUCUGCCUCUGGCUUCGGCACCUUCCCAGCCUUGAAAAAGCAAUGCUGCAUCUUUUUGAAAAGCUAAUCUCCAGUGAGAGAAAUUGUCUGAGAAGGAUCGAAUGCUUUAUAAAAGAUUCAUCGCUGCCUCAAGCAGCCUGCCACCCUGCCAUAUUCCGGGUUGUUGAUGAGAUGUUCAGGUGUGCACUCCUGGAAACCGAUGGGGCCCUGGAAAUCAUAGCCACUAUUCAGGUGUUUACGCAGUGCUUUGUAGAAGCUCUGGAGAAAGCAAGCAAGCAGCUGCGGUUUGCACUCAAGACCUACUUUCCUUACACUUCUCCAUCUCUUGCCAUGGUGCUGCUGCAAGACCCUCAAGAUAUCCCUCGGGGACACUGGCUCCAGACACUGAAGCAUAUUUCUGAACUGCUCAGAGAAGCAGUUGAAGACCAGACUCAUGGGUCCUGCGGAGGUCCCUUUGAGAGCUGGUUCCUGUUCAUUCACUUCGGAGGAUGGGCUGAGAUGGUGGCAGAGCAAUUACUGAUGUCGGCAGCCGAACCCCCCACGGCCCUGCUGUGGCUCUUGGCCUUCUACUACGGCCCCCGUGAUGGGAGGCAGCAGAGAGCACAGACUAUGGUCCAGGUGAAGGCCGUGCUGGGCCACCUCCUGGCAAUGUCCAGAAGCAGCAGCCUCUCAGCCCAGGACCUGCAGACGGUAGCAGGACAGGGCACAGACACAGACCUCAGAGCUCCUGCACAACAGCUGAUCAGGCACCUUCUCCUCAACUUCCUGCUCUGGGCUCCUGGAGGCCACACGAUCGCCUGGGAUGUCAUCACCCUGAUGGCUCACACUGCUGAGAUAACUCACGAGAUCAUUGGCUUUCUUGACCAGACCUUGUACAGAUGGAAUCGUCUUGGCAUUGAAAGCCCUAGAUCAGAAAAACUGGCCCGAGAGCUCCUUAAAGAGCUGCGAACUCAAGUCUAGAAGGCACGCAGGCCGUGUGGGUGCCCGGCGUGAGGGAUCAGGCUCGCCAGGGCCACAGGACAGGUGAUGACCUGUGGCCACGCAUUUGUGGAGUAAGUGCCCUCGCUGGGCUGUGAGAAUGAGCUGUACACAUCUUGGGACAAUCUGCUAGUAUCUAUUUUACAAAAUGCAGAGCCAGGUCCCUCAGCCCAGACUCAGUCAGACAUGUUCACUAAUGACUCAAGUGAGCCUUCGGUACUCCUGGUGCCCGCCCGGCCAGACCGUCAGCUUGAUAAUUACUAAAGCAAAGGCCUGGGUGGGAGAACAGGUUUCUAGUUUUUACCCAAGUCAAGCUGCACAUCUAUUAUUUAAAAAUUCAAAGUCUUAGAACCAAGAAUUUGGUCAUGAACCAUUAAAGAAUUUAGAGAGAACUUAGCUCUUUUUAGACUCUUUUUAGGAGUCAGGGAUCUGGGAUAAAGCCACACUGUCUUGCUGUAUGGAGAAAUUCUUCAAGGGGAGUCAGGGUCCCUCAGGCUUCCCUUGUGUCUCCCUGGACCUGCCUGACAGGCCACAGGAGCAGACAGCACACCCAAGCCCGGGCCUCCGGCACACUCUUUCCACUCUGUAUUUGCUAAAUGAUGCUAACUGCUACCAAAAGGCCCUUGGGACAUCAGAGGAGCCGGCAGGCGAAGGUAGAGGAUGUGUUCCAGAAACAUUAGAAGGCAGGAUUAAUUCAGUUAGUUAGUUCUCUUGUUAAAUGGAAAUGGGAAUUGGAAAUUCCUGAUAAAGAAUUGGCCUGGCUGGGUGCAGUGGCUCACACCUGUGAUCCCAGCACUUUGGGAGGCCAAGGCAGGGGGAUUACUUCAGCCCAGGAGUUCCAGACUGCCUGGCUAACAUGGCAAUACCCUAUCUCUACUAAAAAUACAAAAAUUAUCGGGGUGCAAUGGCAUGCAUCUGUAAUCCCAGCUAUUCAAGAGGCUGAGGCAUGAGGAUCUCUUGAACCCGGGAGGUGGGAGUUGUAGUGAGCCGAGAUCAUGACACUGCACUCCAGCCUGGGCAACAGAGCGAGACCAUCUCUUAAAAAAAGGCAUUGUUAGUGUAAUCUCAAGGUUAACAUUUAUUUCAUGUCAGUACAGGGUGCUUUUUCCUUUCAGGGACAUUCUGGAAUUGUAUUGGUUGUACAUUCUUUUGUGUCUAUUCUGUUUGUCAAGUGAGUCAAGACUUGCUUUUGUCCAUUUUGAUUUGUGUGUAUUAGUCUGAGUCUUGGCUCCGUUUUGAGGUAUGAGCAAAGUUUUGCUGGAUUAGAAGUUAACCUUUAGGGAAAUUCCUUAUUUUGGUAUGUGGCAAUGCUAAUAGAUCCACUGAAGAUCUGGAAAAUUCCAGGAACUUUUCACCUGAGCCUUUCUUCUGAGAAAUGCUGCAGUCAGAAGGGUGUGCUGGUAAAGUAUUUUGGUGGCAGCUGCCAUCAUGGUCAUUGCCUUCAUAUAACAUGCUUCGUGCUCAUGGUCAUUGCCUUCAUAUAACAUGCUUCGUGCCAUCAUGAUCCUUGCCUUCAUAUAACAAACAUGCUUCGUCAGAGGUGUUGGGGUUGAAAAAGGAGCUGCAUGCUUCACUGGAGUUGAGGGCCUCUCUCCUGUUCUGACUUUAAGCCAGAACUUGUGGCUGGGCCAUGGAAGCUGUGACUCCUCUGUGGACAUGGUGGCAGCAGGGAACCCCUAGAGAGAGGGGCCACUGGGACCAGGCCUCCUGUUGUGGAGGGACUCCUGGGACAGUCCUCCACCCUGUCCUGUGGUCCUGUGUACAGGGUUGGCCUCUUCCUCCUCCCCUGCCAGGCCUCUGCCCAUGCCCCUUCCUUCCUUCUCCUGGGACUGGUGAAGCUAGGCAUCUGGAAGACUUCUUCCUAGCCUGGAAGCCCUGACCUCGGCCCAUCUGCAGAAUCUCCCAGUUCCUUCACAGCUGCCGAGUCCUCUCACGGGUGCGGUGGAGGCGGCCUUGCCGGUGGUGCUUUCUGGGCAGCCAGGGGUUCCUGGGUGGGAGGACUGUCCCUCUGGGGACGUGGCACUGAAGUGCCUGCUGGCUUCAUGUGGCCCUUUGCCCUUUCCCAGCCUGAGAGAUGCUCAAAGGUGGGGAGCUGGGGGAGCCACCCCUCGGCCAUUCCCUCCACCUCCAAGACAGGUGGCGGCCGGGCAGGCACUCUUAAGCCCACCUCCCCCUCUUGUUGCCUUCGAUUUCGGCAAAGCCUGGGCAGGUGCCACCGGGAAGGAAUGGCAUCCGAGAUGCUGGGCGGGGACGCGGCGUGGCCGAGGGGGCCUUGACGGCGUUGGCGGGGCCUGGGCACAGGGGCAGCCGCAGGGAGGCAGGGAUGGCAAGGCGUGAAGCCACCCUGGAAGGAACUGGACCAAGGUCUUCAGAGGUGCGACAGGGUCUGGAAUCUGACCUUACUCUAGCAGGAGUUUUUGUAGACUCUCCCUGAUAGUUUAGUUUUUGAUAAAGCAUGCUGGUAAAACCACUACCCUCAGAGAGAGCCAAAAAUACAGAAGAGGCGGAGAGCGCCCCUCCAACCAGGCUGUUAUUCCCCUGGACUCCGUGACAUCUGUGGAAUUUUUUAGCUCUUUAAAAUCUGUAAUUUGUUGUCUAUUUUUUCAUUCUAAAUAAAACUUCAGUUUGCACCUAA